GCUCACACCAACCAAUUCUCCAACUCUCCAGACACCAAGUAGGUGUUCAACAACUCAAUUCAAUUCUGACACUAUCUACCUGGAGUUAGCAUCCUAUCCCUGGAGUUAAGGGCUCAGUCCCUCCCACAAGGCUGCCCCAUAUCAGAUGCUAAUCCCAAGUCCCAGGCCUCCUGUACUUCUGACUGACUGGCUAAAUAUCAAGGGUUCUCAUAACCCCUUUCUUAGGUUCAAUAAUUUGCCAGAACAACUCACAGAACUCAAAAAAGACUGUACUUAUUAUAACCAGUUUAUUGUCAAGAAUACAACUCAAGAACAGCCAAAUGGAAAAGAUGCUUAGGGCAAGGUGUGGAGGAAGGGCAUGGAUCUUCCCAUGUCCUCUCUGGGUGCACAGCCUCCCAGCACCUCCGUAAGCUUUCUGAACCCUGGUUGUUUAGGGGCUUUUAUGGAAGUUCCAUUACAUAGACAUGAUGAACUAAAUCACUGGCCAUUGUUGAUUAGUUCCAAUUCCAGCCCUUUCUCCCCUCCAUGGAGGUUGUAGGGUGAGGCUAAAAGUUCCAACUCCCUAAUGGUGCGUUGGUCUUUCUGGCAACCCGUUCCCCUGAAGCUAUCUAGGGGCCCCCCAACCAUCAGUCAUCACAUUUACUUGCAAAAGGCACUUAUUACUCCCAAAAUUCCAAGGGCUUUAGGAGCUGUGUCAGGAACUGGGGACAAAGACCAAAUUUUUUUUAAUGAUCACAGGACUUUAAAAGGAAAGACAUAGUGUUAGAUGCUAUGGGGAGGGAUGAAGUUGAAGACUUAUUUUCUUCCCUUGAGGUGAAUGGGAGUGAUGGAUGGGUCUCUGUGUAAGACAUGUGGUCAUAGAAUUUAAUAGCCAAAAGAAAUUUGGUAAUCAUUAAAUCUAAUGUAUAUUCUGUGACGGGUUCCUAGGCAACUGCAAAACAUGAAAUUCCAUGGUUAAAUAAGUUUGCUAAAAGUUGCAUACCAUAUGAAGUUUUAUACUGCUUAGUAGCCCAUCGGAAGGUCUGAAAAGUUUUAGAGUAAAGAUUAAACACAUUUUUCUCAGCUCUCCCUACACUUGUCUCCAGAAUCCCUUUUAUCAUGACACAAGUAUUUUCAUUUAUUCAACAAAUAUUUAUUGAACAACUGCUGCUUGGCACUGUACUACGAAAAGUUGGUGUUCUAGAGGACACAGUUUGAGAAAUGAUGAUCUUGUCCAACUUCAGCGAUUUUCAGGUGAGCAAAUUAAGUCUAUGAAUAAUCACAUUUUAGUCAAAGGAGGUAGUUAAAGAGAGAGGCUGAAAGAGGGGGUGCCAUUUCCAUAGGGAAAUCAGUAGGAAAAAUCUACUGCAAGAUAACGGCAAUUAAGAAGCGUAAUAUGGGCUGGGCGCAGUGGCUCACGCCUGUAAUCCCAACACUUUGGGAGGCCGAGGCGGGUAGAUCACGAGGUCCGGAGAUCAAGACCAUCUUGGCCAACAUGGUGAAACCCUGUCUCUACUAAAAAUACAAAAAUUACCUGGGCGUAGUGGCACACGCACUUGUAAUUUCAGCUUCUCGAGAGGCUGAGGCAGGAGAAUCUCUUGAACCUGGGAGGCAGAGAUUGCAGUGAGCCAAGAUCACGCCGCUGCACUCCAGCCUAGCAACAGAGUGAGACUCCGUCAAAAAAAAGAAAGAAAGAAAAAGAAAAAAGAAACAUGAUAAGGAGUUGUAGAAAUGGUUUCAGAGGCAGAUUCAUUUUUUCCUGGGAGUGGCAUAUAAAGAUAAAGGACUAGAUAAGAUGAAAGUGCUUGCAUCUUAGUGGUGAGGAGUUGGUCCACGUGGUAGACAGUCAAUUUUAUGAAGUCAGAGAGGGCGGACAGGUGGAAAUUAGUCAGAUAAAUGCACAUACGCACUCUCUCUCUCAAACGACCCCCAGAGCUGGCAAGAGGCUGGAGAUCAGAUUCACCUGGUACUUUUUUUUAAAUUAUUUUGAGAAGGAGACUCGCUCUGUCACCCAGGCUGGAGUGCAGUGACACAAUCUCGGUUCACCGCAGCCUCUGCUUCCUGGGUUCAAGCGAUUCUCCUGCCUCAGCCUCCUGAGUAGCUGGGACUCUAUAGGUGCGCACCACCACACCCGGCUAAUUUUUGUAUUGUUAUUAGAGAAAGUUUCACCAUGUUAGCUAGGCUGGUUUCGAACUCCUGACCUCAAGUGAUCCAUGCGCCUCGGCCCCCGAAAAUGCUGAGAUUACCACCUGAUGCUUUUUAGCAUUUUGCUGGAUGUACUGAGUGAUGCAGACAUGAGCAACGGAGGUUUCUCCCGGGACUCCGUGGAGGAGGUGAUGCAGCCGCAGCUCCAGGAUCAGCAAACACUGGUGUCCUAAGCAUAGUGGGGUUAUUUCAGAUGUCACAAAACCAAAAUCUCUGUGGCCCAGUGGAGUGUAACAAAAGAUACACAAACCUCUUCCAUGCAGAGAGAUACAUAGCUCUCCGGUAUAGCUAGGGAGAAAGAAGGAAAGAUUUCUCAGAUGGUGAAGGCAGGCCAAUCGAAGAGAAAAGGCCAGAAAUAAAACUCCACCACGAUGAGAAGCAACCUCUGUGAGGAGUUACUGGGGGAAGAGUCCCCUGUGGAAUGAGCACUGAUGUCUCCAUUCAUUGUGCAGGUCCCUCUCACACUGCUUUCAUUACUUGAACACUAUCUGGUGUCAUUAAGAUAUCAAUUUUAUUUAGGUAUAUCUGCAUUGGCAGUUUAAUUAUGUCUGGGUAAGGCCCGAUAUUUAUUCAUGGGUGAUCUUGGUAGUUGUCAGACACCAGCCUGAAGAUAAAGGCGUCCAUGCCUGAGGAAUGCUAAUGCUCCCCAGCCUGUCAUUUGACAAGCGCACAUGCCAGUUACUACCAAACUGAUUAUUUCAAUCAUUAACAACACAUGCAUCAGCCUCCUUCACCCGAGAUUGCCACGUGCAUUCAUCUUUUCAUAAACAGUUAUCUGACAAGGGUGCUGAGAAUUGAUGUUCUGGGGGGAAUUGCCCAACUUGCCUUAGCUACGGAUGCAGCAAGCUGAACGCCCCGCUUAGCAUCGUCAUUUCAUUAAUCAGAUUAGCACAACGCCCAAUUGAGUGAGCACCAUGUUCCUAAACAAUCUCCAAUCAGGGUUCCUUUCUGUUGUCCAUGCUGGUGGCUGCACUUUUUUUUUUUUCCUGGAGGGUUCAGCUUUGCAGAUCCUCUUAGAAAACUUGGAUCUUUGCUUAUCCCACCACCCAUCCCAUUUAUAAUAAUUACUCUUGUUCCAAGGAGCAGGGUGCGGGGAGAGGCUCUGGGUUUGUGGAGGCGCCAUCUGCUCCUUAUUGCUCACCUGAGUCAGAGCCUCCUGACAUCACUUCUCUGCAGCAAUGAGAGCCAGAUAUCCACACAAAGAGGCUGGGGCUGUGCCAGACGGCGCAGGGCCUGAAAAGUGAUGAAUGAAAGAAAUGUGAAACAGUAAAACUGCUCCCAGGCAGCGAGCCCUUCCUUCAAAGGGUGACUCACAGAAAAGGCAGUUUUGCCUUAGUUAGGAAGGUCGUCCCAGACCCCUACAGCUGAAGGACUAGCAUUUGUUUCUCUACACUCACAGCUUGUGCAGAUCGCAUCUCACCCAUCAGGGAAAAGAGAACACUCUGUUCAGUUUCACUAAGGCUUUUUGUUGCUCUUCUUCUUAUGAUGUAAGGCAAACUUCCAGGGUUUGGGUUUUUAAUGGUUUUAUAUGAUUACCUUUUCAUGAGAAGCACAGUUAUAUUUAUAUUUUUAAAGCAAACCCAAAGUAAGAAAAAAUGUAUAUAUUUUCAUCAUAUGAAUGGAAAGCAUUAUAUAUUUUUUCUUUUCUUGGAAUAUUUUCAUUUGAUGACACCAAUGGCAUGAUGAUGAUGAUAAUGUUUUCUAUUUAUUUGAUGCUUUACUAAUAUAUUCUUUUCAAUUUUCACAAAAACUGUACUUUCUUUUUAAAAAGAUUUUUGGAAACUGAGAUGAAGAGACUUUGGGCAACUUGCCCAAGAUAAUGAGCUACUUAGUGGUAACCCUUGAUGAGAGGGUUUUAAAAUCCUACUUUUACCACUUAAAAGUCAUCAUAGAGUCCUGGUAGUCCAACAUUCUUUGUGAUGCUUCGGAAUCCAGAUCGAUGGUUAUUUAUGAGAUGGGAUCUUACCCACUUUUGUUAUGUAGCUCAUUCUCAUUCUUCUUUUGAAAAGCUUUAACAGUUAAAAAUUCCUUUUUUAUCAUUGAGACAAAUUCCUUAUUUUUUAAAACAUUUCCAACCAGUUCUAGAUUUCCUUCUAGAUUCACAGAGAACAAAUCUGAUUCUGCAUGUAUUAGGUUGGUGCAAAAGUAAUCGCGGUUUUUGUCAUUGAAAGUAAUAGCAAAAACUGCAAUUACUUUUGCACCAACCUAAAAGUAGUCACUGUCUUCAGAUAUUUAAAAACAGCCAUAAUGUCUUCUGGAAACUUCUCUUCUUCAGACUGAUUCCAAAUGUUGAAGUUGUGGCACUGUAUUAGUCUGCUUGGGCUAUGUCAGAGAAAAAAAAAUAUUUUUUCUCUACUUCCACACAUCUCUCGAUAUAACACUUCUGACACUACAUUCUCCAGCACACAUCAUCUGGGUGUCUUAUUCAAUUCAGUUCCGACACCAUCAACCUGUAGACAGCAUCAGAUAUCAUAGGUUAAGGGCUCAGUCUCACAAGACUGCCCCCCACUUUAAAUGCUUGUUGCGAUUAGUAUACCUCUGAUUGAUUAUCUGGCUAUAAAUUGGGGUUUUCCAUGAACGCUUCAUUAGAUUUGUUUAAUUUGCUAGAGUGGCUCACAGAACUCGGGGAAACACUUAUGUUGACCCACUUAUUACAAAGGAUAUUACAAAGGAUACAGAGGAGCAGCCAGAUAGAAGAGAUGCAUAGGGCGAGGUAUGUAGGAAGGGGUUUGGAGCUCCCAGAUCCCUGGUUGCACCAACCUCCAGGAACUGCUGUGUGUGCAGCUCUCUGGAAGCUGUCAGAACCCAGUCUUGGGUUCUUGUAGAGGUCUCAUCACAUAGGCAUGAUUGAUUAAACCACUGGCCAUUGGUGAUGAACUCAAUCUUCAGCUCCUCUUUCCACCCCAGAGGUGUGUGUGUGGUGGUAGUGGGGGAGCUGAAAGUUUCAACCCUCUAAUUACAACAUUCCCCUGGCAACCAUCCCCCAUCCUGAGGCUAUCCAGGAGCCCCCAGCCACCAGUCAUCUCAUUAACAUUCACAAAGAAAUUUAUUGCUUUAGAUUCCAAGGGUUUUGGGAAUGAUGAGCCAGGAAACAGGAAGACCAAAUAUCAAAAUAUGGUAGCCUGUGAUAUUUCGAAAUAUCACAGGCUACCAUAACAAAGUGCCACAGGCUGGGGGACCUAAACAACAGUUUAUUGUCUCACAAUUCUGGAGGCUGGAAGUCUGAGAUUGAGGAUGGGUAGGGUUGUUCUCUCCCGCGACCUCUCUCCUUGGCUUGCACAUGGCCACCUUCUCUCUGUGUCUUCACACAACCUUUCCUCUGUGCAGACAUACUCCUGGUAUCUCUUCCUCUUCCUUUAAGAACACCAAUUCUGUUGGAUCAGGGAUCUACUCUUCCAACCUCACUUAACCAUUUUUUUUUUUUUUUUUUGGAAACAGAGUCUCGCUCUGUUGCCCAGGCUGGAGGGCAGUGGCGCAAUCUCUGCUCACUGCAACCUCCACCUCUCCCGAGUUCAAGUGAUUCUCAUGCCUCAGCCUCCCAAGUAGCUGGGACUGCAGGUGCACGCCACCAUGCCCAGCUAUUUUUGUAUUUUUUAUAGGGAUGCAGUUUUGCCAUGCUGGCCAGACUGGUCUCAGACUCCUAACCUCAAGUGAUCCACCUGCCUUGGCCUCCUAAACUGCUGGGAUUACAGGCAUGAACCACUGUGCCCGACCCCUCAUUUAACUUUAAUAACCUCCUUUAAUGCCCUUUAAUCUUCAAAUACAGUCACAUUGAGAGUUGAGGCUUCAACUUACCAAUUUUGAGGGGAUAUAAUUCCGUCCAUUCCAGGUAUCAAUGAAGUCAAGGCAUCCAUUCCUUCAACAUGCUUUACUACAUGUACAGAAACCACAGCAAGUCAAGAUUGUUCACAGUUGAAAGAGGUUUCUGGAGGUGUGUGAACCAUCUGAACUUCAUCCUCUUUCUUCAAGUAGCCUUCAAGAUUUGUGCCCACUGAACGAAUGCUAUGGAAACUGCCAACAGAUGACCAUCUGGUCACGAUGUUCAAAGGCUCAACCUAAACAACAUUGAAAAUUACCAAAACUAAGGCAAAGGGUAUGAUUCUACUAAAGAAAGAGACUCCUUAAGGAGCAAGAGUCUCUAGGAACUGACUCUUCAGCAGUACUGAAUGUAAAAUUGGAAUAACCACCCUCUCAAAUCUCAGAGAAACUGGACUUAGGGCUCUUUUUUUAUUAGAAUGUGUUUGGGAAGGUGGACAGGGUGAUUGUAUCAACUGGCCCUUCCAUUCCCAAUGUGUGUACCAAGAGCGAGUGAGACAGUGAUGAAUUACCCAGGAUGAGGUUAGAAUAAUUUAAUAAAAAGAGGUGGAAAUGGGGUCUUUAAUUCCUAACCUUUUGAGCUGUGGCUAAAAUCCAUUAAUAGAACAUGGAUUAAGAGUCCAAAGUAAGAUUACUCAGCAUCACCCGCCAGUGAAUCACUCUGGCACUUGGGUCAGAAUUAAUAUCUGAGAAUUCUUUGAAACUUUAUGGCUGGAAUUUUUCUUUCCCCCUGGCUUGGCUUCUUUUGUAGUCUUAGCCUCUUUAGCAGAGGAGAUAGGAAAUCUUUGGCAUCCAUUCAAAAACUCAUUCAAACCACAGAGUAGAACUUUAAAGGAGGCCUUUGGGGAUAUGUGGGGUCAGUUGGAAUAGUUUAUAUCAUAGCUUUCAGUUUAAAACAAUUUUUUACAGCAUCAGUAGGGAGAAUUAUAUCACAAUACAUAAAUAGAUUUAGCAGGAUUUACAAAUCCACAUGUGUUCCCUUAAGCAGUAGUUUUCAAAUAUUUGAUGACCUUAGAACUCCUAGUUCAAAUGAAAUUUUACACUGAAGUGAAAAUGAACACUGAUAAAAGGGGAGUUUCUCUGCUUAAAUAAGGAUGUGAGGUCCCAGAGAUCCCUUCUGCCUUUCCCUUUUGCUCUUUUGGGUAGCCCCUAAGGGGAAUGAAUGCCAAGAUCUUCCAGGAAGAUAGAUUGAAUGCUUUUUCUCUAGGAGACUCUUGUUCUACAGUGAAGUUCGCUCAAUGAACCACAGAAAUGUGUGAGCAAAGGCUGAUCAUUAAGUGGUAAGUCACACCUCUCCUUAAGUUUUGAAAAAAUAUUUUGAAAGUGAUAUCUGGUCUUCCAACGUAAAUGCAGAGAUGAAAGAAACAGACUUUUCUUUCUCCACAGCAGGAGCACUUAAAAGUCUUUGACUAUUUAAACUACUGGAAAAAGGUACAUUUUAUCAAUUGAGCAUGCAUUUUUAGUCCAUCAAAUCAUACAAUGUUGAAGAUGGAAGGAACCCUAGAAAUUGAUAUCAAAUGAGGCAAUUACACAAAAUGCUUUGGAACCUGUGAAACAUUUUGCAAGAGUAAAAUUUGAUGAUGAUAUUUAACCCUUUCCACUAACUAGAGCUUUAAUGCACCUUUAAUGUUUAACCCUGAACCCUUUGGCAAGAACUCAGAAAGGGAAAAACCACCCUGCCCAGUGUCAAGCUGCUGGUCAGUGACACAGAUAACACUAGAACAUUAUAGAUUGUUGCUUGAAGACAUUGUGAUCUGUCACAAAAGCCUAGGAAUCAGAGGUCAAUCAGAAAUUAGAAAGAAAUCGUUUACUUUCUCACUCACAAAAAUAUGUUUUAUUUAUACCUAAGGUGGAUCCCAAGGGACUACUUUCUGUUGGAACACAAAAGAGAAGUCUAUCAGUCUUGAUCUGCAAAUCUAAACCAUGUUUUAGAGAGGGGAUUUAGGCUUAUUUACUAACUAAGCCCAAACUGGGGUGCCCAGGAGCACCCUCUCUUUGUAGCUCUAGUGACACAUUUUGAGCAAAUGGGUGGAAUCUCAUCUUACAUGGUUGGUGGUGAGCUUCUAAAAUGAGUAAAGAAGUUAAAGAUCAUACAAAAUCAGAAUUUUUUUCUGAGGACCCUUCAGACUCUUAGAAGCUCAACGACAAAUCAUGUGUUAAUACUAUUGUCUAUGGAAAUUUCACUGACAUGUUCCUUUUCCUGUGACAUUGGAAGCUAACGUCUCUUUCGAAUUGAGGAAGGCAGCAUAAAUAAGGUGUUUUGUCUUCUUUGUGCUUGAUUGCUUGAAUAUGAAUCAUGUGCUCUGAUUCCUAAACAAGUUGCCUGUUUGACUUACAAAUUGACUCAUGGUGCUAGAACUGGUCUGAAGCUCAAGUCAAUUUGAAAUGAGAAUCCAAUAACAAACACGCAGUGAUGUUUAAAGAAAAAGAUGUUCUUUGCCAAUGUCUCUAACCUGUGAAGUGAAAUUAUGGAGAGUGACCACUAACUCCCUGAGCUGACCAUUAGUACCCUCAUCCACGCUAGGGUUGAGAAAAACAUUGGGAGCUAGUACGGUUGACUGUCUCCAUAGAUAUGCCAACUAUUUCUCCCACCCAUAUUUGUGCAUUCCAUUUACCCCAUCCAGAUACGGAAUCAUGGAAUCUAAUUAUGUUCACUCCACUUGGAUUUGAGCUGGCCUUGGGAUUUGCAUCAGCUACUAGAAUGUGGCAGCAGCAAUGUUGUGCCAACUCCAGGCUUAGCCACUUAGAGCCCUGACAGCUUCUGCUGUGGCUCACCUUGGAGCCCUGAGCCACCAAAUAAGGAAUUCAACAACCCUGCUGAGGAGAGGCCCAGACAGCUCCCAGAUCUUCAGCCACCACAGCUGAGGACCCAGAUAUGGACCUGAUGCCCAGAACCCUGGACGGGCAGAUCACCAUGGAGAAGACGCCCAGUUACUUCGUCACGCGGGAGGCCCCCGCGCGCAUCUCGGCCAUGUCCAAGGACACCAAGCUCAUCGUGGUGGUGCGGGACCCGGUGACCAGGGCCAUCUCGGACUACACGCAGACGCUGUCCAAGCGGCCCGACAUCCCCACCUUCGAGAGCUUGACGUUCAAAAACAGGACAGCGGGCCUCAUCGACACGUCGUGGAGCGCCAUCCAGAUCGGCAUCUACGCCAAGCACCUGGAGCACUGGCUGCGCCACUUCCCCAUCCGCCAGAUGCUCUUCGUGAGCGGCGAGCGGCUCAUCAGCGACCCGGCCGGGGAGCUGGGCCGCGUGCAAGACUUCCUGGGCCUCAAGAGGAUCAUCACGGACAAGCACUUCUACUUCAACAAGACCAAGGGCUUCCCCUGCCUGAAGAAGGCGGAGGGCAGCAGCCGGCCCCAUUGCCUGGGCAAGACCAAGGGCAGGACCCAUCCUGAGAUCGACCGCGAGGUGGUGCGCAGGCUGCGCGAGUUCUACCGGCCUUUCAACCUCAAGUUCUACCAGAUGACCGGGCACGACUUUGGCUGGGAUGGAUAACCAUAUAAUUUAAAAAGAAAAAAAAAAUCAAAAUAUAAUAUAUUUUUUUACCAAUCGGUAGAGAAGAGACAGUUUAAUAUUUGUGCUGAAAAUAUGUUUCAGUAUUUUUUUCAAUGAAUGUUAAGAGAUUGUUCUCACUCCCGCCCCAUCUUAAUGUAUAACCAACACCAAACACGUGGAUCAACAGAAAAGGAAAAUUUCACUCGUCUAAACACUUUCAAUUUUCAGUUUUUAUUUUAUGUUCUAUAUACCCAGUCAUAAAGUAUAAGCAUCAGUUGUCAUUAAAAGUUUUCAGAAAAUCUUGAGGUUAAACAUCUCUCUCUCUUUUUUUAAAAUACAAGGCCCUGAUAAAAUUGAUAUCUAUCCUUAUAUUUUUCUCCCUUUUUCCCGUGCCACUUUUUCUUAAAUUAUUUCCCAGUUAGUAUUAUCAUAUGUUUGUACCCGUCACAGUUUUCAUAGUGCUUUCAAAUACACCUUUUUGAUCAUUAAAAUAAAAAAAUAAAUCUUGCUCUGUUGUAUAAGAUCACAAUAGGUAAAUAUUAUUAUCCCCAUUUUACAGAAAGGAAAACUGAGUCUUUGGGAGGUGAAAUAAUGUAUCUAAAGGUCAAAUGUUGGAUGGACCCUGGACAAAAUUCCAUCUUCCACUUGUUCCCUAUUUCAUGUCACUUUUUCCAGGGAGAAUGGAAAAGAAGACAUCUGCACCUUUAGAAAUGGUUAGGUAGUUUUCAGAUGAUAUGAAAAGGGAAAGAGAGCCCCUUGUUUUCUAAAUUCCCAGGCUACCCCUCAUGGCACCCAGUCUCAUUACAUAGUUGUGUCCAAGAAAACCACUGAGACCUGGACACAACCUCUCUUAAGAGCCAGUCUUGCCUCUUGGCUAUUUAAAGUACACUGAGAUAUGGAAAUCUUGACUGAUGAAUGCUUGAUUGAAUUGGAGAGGAAUUAUUGGAUUCUUGCAUGGAGGACAAGGUGGCCAGCCACACUAGGGGUAGCACAAGAUGUGUUAGGAACGUAACUUACCCAUUUGUUGAUUUAAUUGACUUUAAAAAAAAAAAAGAAACAGAUUUCAAUUAGCACUUACAGGUAUGAGUCUCAUUUGUUUUUUAGUUUACCUCUUUUUAAAGAGAGAAAACCUACCUUUCUUUGUAAUAUCUCACUUCUAACUUUGGAGCUAGUACUCUGAAAGAAUUAAUUAGCAGUUCGUUUAAAAUGUUUUUAUUUUUCAUGGAUGGAGGACUAUCAUUUUGUCACUUUAUUCCCCCCUCCCACUUCCUAUUUAUACCAUUUAUAACCUAAUGUUCAGUAAUAUUUGGAAAAAUAUUCUAGGAAAUGCAUUUGUGGGUAAAAUGGUGGCUUUUCCUCUUCUCUCGUCUGUUUCUGCCCAUCCCCCAUUUAAAUCACUCAAAUAAAUCAAUAGUUUAUUAACAGUAUUCCUUUCCUCUCUGAGUGGGUAUUAACAAGAUUAGCAUUAAUGGGAAUUAAAUUGGUUUAGAGAGGAACACAUAUGCACGAAAUAUAUAAAACAUUUAUAAUUAGCCUGUCAGCAACAUUUUAUUAGAAAUUUAAACCCAAGAGGAAAAAUGUCUUCUAUUUCAUGGAAGUUUUCUUUAUCUGCCAAAAUUUAAACGACCAGACACUCUAAAAUAAUAUUCUUUUUCUUCUUUAAUGUUGUCAAUCAAAAGAAACUAAAGUUGUUUUAAAAUAUGCAGUACAAUUGUACAUUUACCAUAGCUGCUGCAUUAGGUGAUGUAAAUAUUUCUUGAGAAGCUUAACACAGGAUUAAAAUGAAGGAAAAAAUAUUUUAAGUGUUAGAUAUUUUGUCAUUGCUCCAAAUCUUUGGAUUUAUCUGUUAAUAUCCCAUUUAUAGAAGUUAAGUAAACCCCAAAUCCAGGUCACCUUUUUUCAGUUGAUUUCCUUCAUGUCUAUGCUCUCAAUUUCCCAGUGCCACAGACUGUUUUUAUUCUACUUGAAUCACUAGCUGCAACAAGAUACUCAUUUUAAACUCUUGUCAUCAUUUCUCUUAGCUCAUUUUGUUUGUACAACUGAUUCUUUUGUAAGUGUUUGCUUGGCAUUAUGCAAAAGUGGCUUGCACAAAGAAACAAUUGCAUUCUGCAACCUUCAUUUUUUUAAUGUGAAAGAAAUAAAAGAACAGAAUUGAAUGCAAAGGA